AUCCUCAGGAAACCCUGGUACUGGCAGCAGCCAGCCUCUGCUGUGCCCACAUGACCCACAACUCUGGCAGCGGACCCGGCACUUCCAACAUUAUUAAAUAAUAAGAAAGCGGCUCCUACUCCAGGCUCAAACCUCCCUGCAGACCAAUGGACACCUUCUAAGAGUUUGGCGAGUCAGUGACUGAAGCGCCCGUCCAUUCCAAGAUAAAUAGGAUUUACCAAUCCUUGGAUGAAGUGCUUGGGAAGUCUUUAAGUGCCAUAAUCAACUGCCAUUUCAAAGAAUAUAGAUGGUUUUGAAAAGUUCAUGCUGUCCCUUCAUUGAAUUUUAGAGGUCAUCUCAACUGCUCAUCUGUCCAUUUUAAUGUACUGUGGUUGGACUCUGAAGGACAUGAUGUUCCUUCUACCAACAAUUUUCAUCUAUUCAACCAAUGUCAAUGUUGAACCUGCAAUGCCUAAUUUAGAAUCCUUUCAGACAAUGCGCAAAUGCCAUCAUGAACAGAAUUUCUAAAACUCCUUCAUCAUCCUAAAGCUGGGAGACACAGAAUGAUUGAAGAUAGUGGGAAAAGAGGAAAUACCAUGGCAGAAAGAAGACAGCUGUUUGCAGAGAUGAGGGCUCAAGAUCUGGAUCGCAUCCGACUCUCCACCUACAGAACAGCAUGCAAGCUUAGGUUUGUUCAGAAGAAAUGCAAUUUGCACCUGGUGGACAUAUGGAAUGUCAUAGAAGCAUUGCGGGAAAAUGCUCUGAACAACCUGGACCCAAACACUGAACUCAACGUGUCCCGCUUAGAGGCUGUGCUCUCCACUAUUUUUUACCAGCUCAACAAACGGAUGCCAACCACUCACCAAAUCCAUGUGGAGCAGUCCAUCAGCCUCCUCCUUAACUUCCUGCUUGCAGCGUUUGAUCCGGAAGGCCAUGGUAAAAUUUCAGUAUUUGCUGUCAAAAUGGCUUUAGCCACAUUGUGUGGAGGGAAGAUCAUGGACAAAUUAAGAUAUAUUUUCUCAAUGAUUUCUGACUCCAGUGGGGUGAUGGUUUAUGGACGAUAUGACCAAUUCCUUCGGGAAGUUCUCAAACUACCCACGGCAGUUUUUGAAGGUCCUUCAUUUGGUUACACAGAACAGUCAGCCAGAUCCUGUUUCUCCCAACAGAAAAAAGUCACGUUAAAUGGUUUCUUGGACACGCUUAUGUCAGAUCCUCCCCCGCAGUGUCUGGUCUGGUUGCCUCUUCUGCAUCGACUAGCAAAUGUGGAAAAUGUCUUCCAUCCGGUUGAGUGUUCCUACUGCCACAGUGAGAGUAUGAUGGGAUUUCGCUACCGAUGCCAACAGUGUCACAAUUACCAGCUCUGUCAGGACUGCUUCUGGAGGGGACAUGCCGGUGGUUCUCAUAGCAACCAGCACCAAAUGAAAGAGUACACGUCAUGGAAAUCACCUGCUAAGAAGCUGACUAAUGCAUUAAGCAAGUCCCUGAGCUGUGCUUCCAGCCGUGAACCUUUGCACCCCAUGUUCCCAGAUCAGCCUGAGAAGCCACUCAACUUGGCUCACAUCGUGCCUCCCAGACCUGUAACCAGCAUGAACGACACCCUGUUCUCCCACUCUGUUCCCUCCUCAGGAAGUCCUUUUAUUACCAGGAGCAUGCUUGAGAGUUCAAACCGGCUUGAUGAAGAACACAGGCUAAUUGCCAGGUAUGCGGCAAGGCUGGCAGCAGAGUCCUCUUCGUCUCAGCCACCUCAGCAGAGAAGUGCUCCUGACAUCUCUUUCACCAUCGAUGCGAAUAAGCAGCAAAGGCAGCUGAUUGCUGAGCUAGAAAACAAGAACAGAGAAAUCUUACAGGAGAUCCAGAGACUUCGGCUAGAGCAUGAACAAGCUUCUCAGCCCACGCCAGAGAAGGCACAGCAAAACCCCACCCUGCUGGCAGAACUCCGGCUCCUCAGACAGCGCAAAGAUGAGCUGGAACAGAGAAUGUCUGCUCUCCAGGAGAGCCGGAGAGAGCUAAUGGUCCAGUUGGAGGGUCUCAUGAAGCUACUAAAGACUCAGGGGGCAGGCUCUCCCCGCUCCUCCCCCAGCCACACCAUCAGCAGGCCAAUUCCCAUGCCCAUCCGGUCAGCGUCAGCCUGCUCCACCCCGACGCACACGCCGCAGGACUCCCUCACAGGAGUAGGGGGAGAUGUACAAGAGGCAUUUGCACAAAGUUCAAGAAGAAACUUAAGGAAUGACUUGCUAGUGGCUGCAGAUUCCAUCACUAACACUAUGUCCUCUCUUGUGAAAGAGCUGAAUUCUGAGGUUGGGAGUGAAACAGAGAGUAAUGUGGAUUCUGAAUUUGCACGGACUCAGUUUGAGGAUCUUGUUCCCUCACCAACCUCUGAAAAGGCUUUUCUAGCGCAAAUCCAUGCCCGAAAACCUGGGUACAUUCACAGUGGAGCUACCACAAGUACCAUGCGUGGCGACAUGGUUACGGAGGAUGCAGAUCCCUAUGUGCAGCCUGAAGAUGAAAACUAUGAAAAUGACUCUGUCCGGCAGCUGGAGAAUGAGCUCCAGAUGGAGGAAUACCUGAAACAGAAGCUGCAAGAUGAAGCUUAUCAGGUCAGCUUGCAAGGUUGAAUGCAAUAUCCUUUUAUCACACUCCUCUCAAGCAAGCUAUAGUCAGACAGAUGAUGAAAGUAACAUGAAAACUGGUGAUGAUGGAGAGCCCUGUGGCCACACAGAGGAGGAAGACAGCAGCCUGGCAGCAGCCUCACCGAAGAGAGGAACCACCACACCCAGCAGCUCCUGACAGACCCCCACCCCUAAAGAUGUGUCCUGAUGACUAUAGUGCAGCUAACUUUUUGUUCUCAGAUUUGUAGUGCAUAGGUGUGUGUUUCAAGAAGGAAAAAAAAAGACUUCUGUUCAAAGUUAACUUAUCAGCUACAUCCUCUGUAACGUGGUUCAUCCCUGGUUAAAAAGCAAACAAACACAGGCUGAAAACCCAUGCUGCUGUUAUACACAAUGGCAGUAUUAACAAGCAUUUUAAACCUUUGCACAUGAUAUUGAACCUGUUCAGUUUACAAUGACAAUAUUAAUACUGUUUAUAGCUAGAAGUUUGAUUUCUGAAUUCUUUGAGAUUUUAGCAAAACAGUUUAUUAUACACUGUACAUUUUUUUCACAGCAAUUGGAAAAAAACAACCACUUGCAAUCAUUCAAUAACCCUGAAGAAUUUGGUUCCUGAGUGUACAAACUCAGAGCCCGGAAGCCAAGAAGGGUCCUUGGCCUGCACGGUCUGUAGUUGACUCCAAGUCUCUGUGAGCAGUGACUUGAACCAAACACACCAGGAAUAAUCCAUUCUUUGGGGCCUCUUUCCAACUCGAGGUUGUUUUCUUUCAAGAUACUCUAAUCAGCCAUAGAAUUUAGUGUAAAUAUUUUUUUUUCCAAAUAGAUAUCAUAUUCAAAAAAGGCAGCAUUCAAAUUAUAUAGAAUCUAGUUUUUAAAAUCAGCACAGAUCUUCUUAAAAACUGUGAACUAUGUUUUGAAAUACUCGUUACUAAAGCUGUUUAUAAACCACAGGUGCCAUAAGAUCCCCAAACGGACUAAAGUUAUCUCUGCUCUUCCAUGGUCUUGUUCCUCUCGUUUUGGCUUUAGGAAGCAUGUCUUUAACAGCACCGCUCGUUCACAAGUUCCCCCAUCAAGUUGUUUGGAGGCCUUCAGCUUUAAAUGUACAGGCUUAAAGUGCGCUUGCAAACGUUUGCUCUCCUUUUUUUCUGAAUGUUGAUUGCCUUAGCUGGCCACCUGGUGUUCUGCAUGUAGCCUUCUGUGGUCAUGUGAAAGGAGACAGGCUCUUCUAAGUUGAGUUGGGAUUUUUGCACUCAGUGAAAAGCUGAAGUGCAAAAGAGCUAUCAAAGACAAGAGGAUAAAAGACUGGGAUAGUCUUUUCCAAGGACCCUCUUUAGAGGGCCCUAAAGACCUCCUUUGGGAAUUCUGGGGAAAAAGAAAAAGUAAUCUUCUACUUGCUUCAAGAUUUGAUUUUUUUAAAAAAGCCUGCGACCUAUUCAAUACAUUAUGCUUAAAUUAGCAGUUUCUCUGGAAUUCCUGUCUCUCCUUUAAAAGAAAGGAGAGAACAUUUUAGAACAAUAGUUCUCAAAGUGUGUUCCCCGGACAAGCAGCAUCUGCAACACUUAGGAAGGUCUUCGAAAUACUAAUUUGUAAGCCCCACCUCAGGCCUACUGAAUCAGAAGCUCUGGGGGUUGGGUCCAGAAGUCUGUUUUAGUCAACCCUCUAGGUGAUUCUGAUGCUCGCUAAAGGUUGAGAACUACUGCUUUAGAAUGAAGUCGUAUAAUAAAGUCUCUGAAAAGGCCUUAUUCAGAAUAAGCAAGAAAGGUUCUGUGAUUCACUUUUGCUUCUGGGGCUGGCAAAAACCUUCUCUGAACCCACACACCAAGUUCGUAGUUGGUAGGUGCCCAGCCAAGUCCUGACAUCUUCAUGCCCCCUCUGCAGAGGGCGGCUGUACGAUGUUCACAUGUCUGCGUUUGGUCAGACAUCAUCUCCUUGGCUGCCCUUUGAAACCAAAUCACUUGCCUUGGGGAUAAAGUGCUCAAUUGGCAUUAGUGAGAAGCCCAUCCUAUCCCUUGACAUACUUAAUCAUAUAUCUCUCCAGAGAACUCACCUGACAAAUGUCUCUGAGCACAGGCUGACACCAAAGUGGCACAACUGCACAGUUCUCAGAUUUCUUUGCACAGAUUGAUUUUUAUUGCGGGUUUUGUUGGGGUGUCUUAAUGUUCAUCUCUUUUCCACUGCCCAUCCUCUGUGAACCCAUACCUCUCUAGAUGGAGCAGGUGGCCACUGGUGCCUCAUACUCAGUAUUGAAAACCACUACAUCCCAGCUACCUAUAAUGCUGUCAGCUCAAAAUCAUAGCCAGGUAGUUCUUGAACUCAGAACUUAAAUCCUGCACGUGGCACUCCACCACUGACUGGACCGAGCUGGCAUAUGUUGUUUCUUUGUGUUUCUACAUCAAAAUGUUCGUCUAAGAUUUGAACUGUUCUGCUGAUAACCUUCCCCGUUGUCAUAGCUAUUUCAUUGCCAACCAACUCCAUCACAUGGUUGUUGAUAUCGUCAUAUAAAGCCAUUGCAAGGACUCUGGAAACUGCCGCCAAUGACCAAUUUCUGACUAACCAGCCACCUUUUCUCUCUCUUAGCUCCACGUCAGCACUGAGACCAGACUCGAGCACCCCUGUCCUGUAAGCGAGACAAAAUGGCGUGUGUUAUUUUGGGGUUUUGUGUUUUUUGGUGGGUUUCUUUCCUUGGCUCUCCAGAUUUACUUUUGGGGCCUGUUCUAAGUGCAAACCCAGCAAGUUUCACUUGUCCUGUCCAUUAGAUACAACUACAUCUUGCGGGGGUUGUUUCUUUCUUGUUCCACAAUGAAUUGCACAUCCAUCUCCAUCAGAGCUGAUAGCCUGUUAAUAAGCACUGGUCUAACACAGCCAACCCUCCUCCACAGCGCCAUAUUAAUGGAGGAGGGGAGGAAGGUGAAAUCUACUGCAUGGGAUUCAGGAAACAGUUGUGGUUGGUCAGGACGGAAGUUGGGGUAAGUUUGGUUGGUCAGAGGGAGUUGUGCUGGAGAUUGUGAAAAAUGGGUUCUUGAAUGAUCUACUAUAAGGCAGGGAAGGUUCAUUUGUAAGUAGUAAUGUGAACUGAAUUGCAUUAAGAGUGUGUGGCCUUUGUUGUGAUAUACUAUGUAUUUUCUUAUAUGCAUGAGCCAAACUGUUGCAUCAUAAUUUAGCACUGAUGUCUGCUUUUAUUUUGAUCAUCUUUGUCCACCCUUAUUAGUUCUUGGCUGUUAACCGUAGAUAGAUCUUGUAAAUCCAGCAACCUUUGGUUGCUGCAUUCCCCUUGGUUCGAUUCCACGCAAGGAGCCACAAGUGAGAACUCCACUGUCCUUAGAAGAAAGGGCAUUUUUACUUUUGAACCAAAAAGAGAAAAAAAAAUCAGAAGUGUUGCAUCUUGAGGCGAAUUAACUGUAAGACAUUUUUAAUUAUGACUACUGCAAUUUGACACCAUUUGAAAUAAUCAAUUCAGAGACACUAAAGAUUUCACAAUAUUCAUUGGUAUUGUAAAAAAAAAAUACUAUUGUAUGGAUUUUUGUAUUGCUGUUAAGUAUUGUUUUGUGUGUGUGUGUGUGUGUGUGUGUUGGAACCUCCUGGGGACAUGUUAUAUUUUGAAGUGAUUAAACUAUUUAAUUGUGUGUCUAUAUUUUGGAGUGGAAUAAUUUCUUCAUUAAAAAAUGUUUUUAAAAACACUAUAUCUUGGGUGGUUUAUUCCUUUGUUUCAGUGAAUCUUUCCUAAAGCAACGUGGAGUCAGUCUGUUGAAAGAAGGAAGGCAGGUACUUGCAGUUUAAAGCAGGACCCAUUGAUGGAAUAUUGAGCCACCGAGGCAAAAUAGCUCACCUUCUCUUGCCUUGGGGGAUGCAUGGUUUUUACCAUUCUACUGUUUUAUUAGCAUCUGUGAGCAUCUAAUAGAAAUACUAUUCUGCUAUUUAUGGAAAUCCUUAUUAUAAUUGAUAUGGAAGUGAGUUUGAAAUUCUAACAGCUAACAUAUUUCAUGUUUGUAUCACACACUGUUCUUAACACUUUAUGUGACUUCACUCAAUUCUUUGAAUCCUCUGCAUCUAGCCAUGUAUUCUGCAAAUAUUAAGUGCUCAAUGGUUUUUUUGUUGAAUUACUGAAUAAAUGAAUUAGUGGUG